GUUGUGGGCAGGCGCCUGAGGCUGACGGCUGGCAAGCAGGGCACCGCGGUGCGCUGAAGCUAGAGAUUCCGAAAGGGGGUUCGGGUAGUUCGCUCCGGAGAAGUCUGAGAAGGGUGGCUCCGGUGAUCCCAGCCCUAGCUGUUUCCCAUAUUCCUUUAUCCACCUGCCUUUGAAGGAGACCAGACUCCGGCUCCGCCCGGCCCGUGCCGGGUGGUCUGCGGCCCCGAGUCCGUGACCAAGCCCUCCGAGUGAUCGGCCUGCCCUCGGGUGCACCCGCGGGUCCCAACGUGGGGGAUCCCUCCAUCCGCAAAGCCAGAGGUCUCUUUGGUCAUGAUGUAGUUGAGCUCCCUGAGGUCCUGGCUGGCUCUGGAUUGCUCCUGCUGAUCCUGCUCUGACAGCGUUUGGGGGGCUAGAAGUGAUUCAUUGGCAGAGUCUGUUAGAGUCCUCAAAGAACAGCCUUGGAAAGCACCUGAGGAAACGUCUCUAAGUUUCCCUAGAACAGGAAAAGGAUAAUGCCAAGGCCUCACUAUGGGUCGGUGGCAAAUAUGGGCCCCAACCCAGGUCAUCUGGCUUGUCUGUCUCCACCUCAUCCUGCUGCUCAAUGUUUAGUCAACAAAGAACAAGGAGUACUGAGUGCCUGCUGUGGGCUCAGGACACAGAUGGAAGAACUAGAAAGACGCAGCCCCUCACCUCAUGGAAUUCACUAGAAAGAUGUGGCCCCUGACCCCAUGGAACUCACUAGAAAGAUGUGGCCCCUGCCCCCAUGGAACUCCAUGAAACUAGGAAGACGCAGUCCCUGGCUCCAUGGAACUCGCUAGAAAGACACUGACCCUUACCCCAUGGAACUCACUAGAAAGACACAGCCCCUGCCUCCAUGGAACUCAAUAGAAAGACGCAGCCCCUGCCCCCGUGGAACUCACUAGAAAGACGCAGCCCCUGCCCCCGUGGAACUCACUAGAAAGACGCAGCCCCUGCCCCCGUGGAACUCACUAGAAAGACGCAGCCCCUGCCUCCGUGAAACUCACUAGAAAGACGCUGUCCCUGACCCCGUGGAACUCACUGGAAAGUCGCAGCCUCUGCCCCCGUGGAACUCACUAAAAAGAUGCAGCCUCUGCCCCCAUGGAACUCACUAGAAAGUUGCUGCCUCCAUGGAACUCUCUAGAAAGACCCAGCCGCUGCCUCCGUGGAACUCACUAGGGAGACACAGCCCCUGCCUCCAUGGAACUCAUGGUCCAGCAGACCAGCUGCAUGCUCUGUGUUACUGCACUACCUGUCCCGGGUGUUGGGGGCUGUGACAAAUUCCCCAGUCCCUAACUUCUCUCCUGUGCCCCAGGGUCCUAAAGAUCGCUCUGGGAAAAGGGAAGGAUGCCGCUCUUCUUCCGGAAGCGGAAACCCAGUGAGGAGGCUCGGAAACGCCUGGAGUACCAGAUGUGUUUGGCAAAAGAAGCUGGGGCAGAUGACAUUCUCGACAUCUCUAAAUGUGAGCUCUCAGAGAUUCCAUUUGGAGCUUUUGCAACAUGCAAAGUUCUGCAGAAGAAGGUGCUGAUCGUCCACACGAAUCACCUCACUUCCCUGCUUCCCAAAUCCUGCAGCCUCCUGAGUCUGGCAACCAUCAAGGUUCUAGAUCUCCACGAUAAUCAGCUGACAGCCCUUCCUGACGAUCUGGGGCAGCUGACUGCCCUCCAGGUCUUAAACGUGGAAAGGAAUCAACUGAUGCAGCUCCCACGUUCCAUUGGGAACCUGACCCAGCUCCAGACUCUCAAUGUUAAAGACAACAAGCUGAAGGAGCUUCCAGACACCGUGGGGGAGCUUCGAAGCCUGCGUACCCUCAACAUCAGUGGAAACGAGAUCCAGAGAUUGCCGCAGAUGCUGGCUCACGUUCGAACCCUGGAGAUGCUGAGCCUUGACGCCUCGGCCAUGGUCUACCCGCCGCGGGAGGUGUGUGGUGCCGGCACUGCGGCCAUCUUGCAGUUCCUCUGCAAAGAGUCAGGGCUGGAAUACUACCCCCCUUCUCAGUACUUGCUGCCAAUUCUGGAGCAAGAUGGAAUCGAGAACUCUCGGGACAGCCCUGAUGGGCCCACGGACAGAUUCUCAAGGGAGGAGUUAGAGUGGCAGAACAGGUUCUCAGACUAUGAGAAGAGGAAGGAACAGAAGAUGCUGGAGAAACUCGAGUUUGAACGGCGCCUGGAACUGGGGCAGCGGGAGCACACCCAGCUCCUUCAGCAGAGCAGCAGCCAGAAGGAUGAGAUCCUUCAGACGGUCAAGGAGGAGCAGUCCCGGCUGGAGCAGGGCCUGAGUGAGCACCAGCGCCACCUCAACGCAGAGCGGCAGCGGCUGCAGGAGCAGCUGAAGCAGACGGAACAGAACAUUUCCAGCCGGAUCCAGAAGCUGCUGCAGGACAAUCAGAGACAAAAGAAAAGCUCCGAGAUUUUGAAAUCGCUGGAAAAUGAAAGAAUAAGAAUGGAACAGUUGAUGUCCAUAACCCAGGAGGAGACUGAGAGCCUGCGGCGACGUGACGUUGCCUCCGCCAUGCAGCAGAUGCUGACUGAGAGCUGUAAGAACCGGCUCAUCCAGAUGGCCUACGAAUCUCAGAGGCAGAACUUGGUCCAGCAGGCCUGUUCCAGCAUGGCCGAAAUGGAUGAACGAUUCCAGCAGAUUCUGUCGUGGCAGCAAAUGGAUCAGAACAAAGCCAUCAGCCAGAUCCUGCAGGAGAGCGCGAUGCAGAAGGCUGCGUUCGAGGCACUCCAGGUGAAGAAAGACCUGAUGCAUCGGCAGAUCAGGAGCCAGAUUAAGUUAAUAGAAACUGAGUUAUUGCAGCUGACACAGCUGGAGUUAAAGAGGAAGUCCCUGGACACAGAGUCACUCCAGGAGAUGAUCUCGGAGCAGCGCUGGGCCCUCAGCUCCCUGCUCCAGCAGCUGCUCAAAGAGAAGCAGCAGCGAGAGGAAGAGCUCCGGGAAAUCCUGACGGAGUUAGAAGCCAAAAGUGAAACCAGGCAGGAAAAUUACUGGCUGAUUCAGUAUCAACGGCUUUUGAACCAGAAGCCCUUGUCCUUGAAGCUGCAAGAAGAGGGGAUGGAGCGCCAGCUGGUGGCCCUCCUGGAGGAGCUGUCGGCUGAGCACUACCUGCCCAUCUUUGCGCACCACCGCCUCUCACUGGACCUGCUGAGCCAAAUGAGCCCAGGGGACCUGGCCAAGGUGGGCGUCUCAGAAGCUGGCCUGCAGCACGAGAUCCUCCGGAGAGUCCAGGAACUGCUGGAUGCAGCCAGGAUCCAGCCAGAGCUGAAACCACCAAUGGGUGAGGUCGUCACCCCUACGGCCCCCCAGGAGCCUCCUGAGUCUGUGAGGCCAUCCGCUCCCCCUGCAGAGCUGGAGGUGCAGGCCUCAGAGUGUGUCGUGUGCCUGGAACGGGAGGCCCAGAUGAUCUUCCUCAACUGUGGCCACGUCUGCUGCUGCCAGCAGUGCUGCCAGCCACUGCGCACCUGCCCGCUGUGCCGCCAGGACAUCGCCCAGCGCCUCCGCAUCUACCACAGCAGCUGAGUGCUGCCCGCCCACCUGGGCCUGGUCCUAGCCCUGCCUCGGCCACUGUGAGCCCCGGGCUCCUGCUCAGCCUUGUGCCAGCCAGACUCGUAUGAGGCUCCCCCCUGCCCUGGGCCCCUUCCCCACUGCCCAGGAGCCCCCAUCCUAAGCUCCAAGCAUGUCUGGGCCAGGCAGAGGUGCUCCUCAUCCAUGACACCACCAGUCUGAAUGGUCCUGGGGGCUGGGGCUGGAGAGGCCGCUGCACCACCACCCGAGCCUGGGAGCCAGCGUCCCAGCCUAAUCACGGAUCUGCUGCCUCCCAGCUGUCUUGACUGAAGGCCACCGCCCCUGCAGGAGCUUGGGUCCUCAUCUGGGGGCCAUGCACAGGCCCGUCCCACCCUGCAUGUGGGAAGGGAGCAGGAGGGCCUGGCUGGGUGAGGGGAGGCCUUCCUGGGAAGGCGUGUGGUGCAGGCCUGUGCUCACAGUGGCACCAGCAACCCUGGGUCUCCCUCUCUGCUGCUCCCCAGAACCCCGGGGCCCUCCUGCUCUCCACAACUGUCCCUCCUUACCCCAUGUAGCUCGAUCCGAAGCAGGAGUGUCAAUAAACCUGUCUUCAGUGCG